GCUCGAACUGGCUCCAGAGCCGUGAGUUCGGCAUGCAAGAGCGGAAGAAACGCGGCUGGUACCCCGGAAGCAGUCGCUGCAACUUCCGGGAGGUGCUUGUGUGCCUGGUGCGGGAGCUACGGGGCCCAGGGAUUGUGUUUAAAGUAGUGCUUCUACCAACAUGUCCCGUGGUUCCAGCGCCGGUUUUGACCGCCACAUUACCAUUUUUUCACCCGAGGGUCGGCUCUACCAAGUAGGUGAGUGAACCAGGUUCGCCUGUGGGCCACCUGAAUUGCCCUGUCAUGAAUAUGCUUUUAAGGCUAUUAACCAGGGUGGCCUUACAUCAGUAGCUGUCAGAGGGAAAGACUGUGCAGUAAUUGUCACACAGAAGAAAGUACCUGACAAAUUAUUGGAUUCCAGCACAGUGACUCACUUAUUCAAGAUAACUGAAAACAUUGGUUGUGUGAUGACCGGAAUGACAGCUGACAGCAGAUCCCAGGUACAGAGGGCACGCUAUGAGGCAGCUAACUGGAAAUACAAGUAUGGCUAUGAGAUUCCUGUGGACAUGCUGUGUAAAAGAAUUGCCGAUAUUUCUCAGGUCUACACACAGAAUGCUGAAAUGAGGCCUCUUGGUUGUUGUAUGAUUUUAAUUGGUAUAGAUGAAGAGCAAGGCCCUCAGGUAUAUAAGUGUGAUCCUGCAGGUUACUACUGUGGGUUUAAAGCCACUGCAGCGGGAGUUAAACAAACUGAGUCAACCAGCUUCCUUGAAAAAAAAGUGAAGAAGAAAUUUGAUUGGACAUUUGAACAGACAGUGGAAACUGCAAUUACAUGCCUGUCUACUGUUCUAUCAAUUGAUUUCAAACCUUCAGAAAUAGAAGUUGGAGUAGUGACAGUUGAAAAUCCUAAAUUCAGGAUUCUUACAGAAGCAGAGAUUGAUGCUCACCUUGUUGCUCUAGCAGAGAGAGACUAAACAUUGUCGUUAGUUUACCAGAUCCGUGAUGCCACUUACCUGUGUGUUUGGUAACAACAAACCAACAUCAUGGAGGUCCCUGGAUUGAAAAAGGAGCCUCUCCCACUCCUCCUACCACCGAAGUGGUUAGGACUCUAUAUAAAUAAAAACAAGGCUUUUGGAAAAUAAUUGCA